CUGCUUUCUUCUGCUGCCUUUUAUGCUCCUUGUGCACCUCCCUUCCCCCCAACCUGGGAUGAAAUCUCCCCACGUGCUGGUGUUCCUUUGCCUCCUGGUGGCUCUGGUCACCGGGAACCUGGUUCAGUUUGGGGUGAUGAUCGAGAAGAUGACAGGCAAGUCCGCCCUGCAGUACAACGACUAUGGCUGUUACUGCGGCAUCGGUGGCUCCCACUGGCCGGUGGACCAGACUGACUGGUGCUGCCACGCCCACGACUGCUGCUACGGGCGUCUGGAGAAGCUGGGCUGUGAGCCCAAACUGGAAAAGUAUCUUUUCUCUGUCAGCGAACGUGGCAUUUUCUGCGCCGGCAGGACCACCUGCCAGCGGCUGACCUGCGAGUGUGACAAGAGGGCUGCCCUCUGCUUUCGCCGCAACCUGGGCACCUACAACCGCAAAUAUGCCCAUUAUCCCAACAAGCUGUGCACCGGGCCCACCCCGCCCUGCUGAGGCUAUGCUCGGCCUCCCCCCCGUCCCUGGAGGUCCCGCCUCGGGCUGCUGUAGUCCCAGGCCUGGGGAACAUUGGCACCAAAGGCCCUCCCUUUGGAAAAUUCCUUUCCUGCAAACUCAUCCCUCCUUGAGAGCUCAGAGAUAUGUCCUGGACCAUCACUAGCCUCCCAGGCUACCCCUUCUCUGUAGAAAGAACCCUGCCCCAGGAGCCAUGGACCCUUCAGCACCCAGAAGACUGUCACUAGCUUCUGGGAUCUCAGCUCCCUCUUCUGAAUAAGUGAAUAAUGUUUUCCCAUAA